ACGGCCGCGGCGGCGGCGGCGGCGGCGGCUGCUGGAGCCCGGAUGCGGCGCCGUGAGGCAGGCCCGGGAGAGCGGCGCGGAUGGAUCCAACAUGGCGGCGCCGAGCCUGAGCCGAGAGAAGAGACCUGGGAAAUUAAGUUUCUUGCGGAGUACGGUGGGGAUUGCAGCUGCUGAGCAGGGAUUCUGGAAAGCAUUGCGUACCUGAGCCCCCAGCAUGGCGGGCCUAAAGCGGCGGGCAAGCCAGGUGUGGCCAGAAGAGCAUGGUGAGCAGGAACAUGGGCUGUACAGCCUGCACCGCAUGUUUGACAUCGUGGGCACUCAUCUGACACACAGAGAUGUGCGCGUGCUUUCUUUCCUCUUUGUUGAUGUCAUUGAUGACCACGAGCGUGGACUCAUCCGAAAUGGACGUGACUUCUUAUUGGCACUGGAGCGCCAGGGCCGCUGUGAUGAAAGUAACUUUCGCCAGGUGCUGCAGCUGCUGCGCAUCAUCACUCGCCACGACCUGCUGCCCUACGUCACCCUCAAGAGGAGACGGGCUGUGUGCCCUGAUCUUGUAGACAAGUAUCUGGAGGAGACAUCAAUUCGCUAUGUGACCCCCAGAGCCCUCAGUGAUCCAGAACCAAGGCCUCCCCAGCCCUCUAAAACAGUGCCUCCCCACUAUCCUGUGGUGUGUUGCCCCACUUCGGGUCCUCAGAUGUGUAGCAAGCGGCCAGCCCGAGGGAGAGCCACACUUGGGAGCCAGCGAAAACGCCGGAAGUCAGUGACACCAGAUCCCAAGGAGAAGCAGACAUGUGGUGAGGAAGUUCAAGGGUUCCAGAGAUGGAGCAGACUUGAAGGAGAAUAUAAAGAACUGCUGGGACACUGGGCAGUUUAUGCUAUUCAGUACAUCAGACUGCGGGUUCGGGCUGAAUACUGCCAGCAUGAGACUGCUCUGCAGGGCAAUGUCUUCUCUAACAAGCAGGACCCACUUGAGCGCCAGUUUGAGCGCUUUAACCAGGCCAACACCAUCCUCAAGUCCCGGGACCUGGGCUCCAUCAUCUGUGACAUCAAGUUCUCUGAGCUCACCUACCUCGAUGCAUUCUGGCGUGACUACAUCAAUGGCUCUUUAUUAGAGGCACUUAAAGGUGUCUUCAUCACAGACUCCCUCAAGCAAGCUGUGGGCCAUGAAGCCAUCAAGCUGCUGGUAAAUGUAGACGAGGAGGACUAUGAGCUGGGCCGACAGAAACUCCUGAGGAACUUGAUGCUGCAAGCAUUGCCCUGACCUAUUCCCUCUUCUCACUUUGGGGACUGUUCCCAUCACCCACCUCUGGAGCUUACACUGUUCUGGGGUUUGUUCUCUACCCUUCCAACCAAUCACACCCCUGCCUUUUUUUUUUUUUUUUUAAAGAAAAAGACAAAAGAAAGUGGAAGUGGUAUUCCCCACCCCUCCCUGCACCCAUGUGCCUGGGCUUCCCCUUUAUUUCCCUUUUCCAUUUACCCCGUAAUGUGUCUCUACAGCUACCUUACCACUGAGCCGUAAGACAAAUGUAUAGGAAGAAGCAAAGUCUACAGCACAUAGUCUUUGUAAGGGAUUGAUGUGAACACUUUUUUUUGGAUGCACUAAGGAGUUAUCAAUACUUCUGGCUUUAUGAGAGCUCUUAAAUUUUGUCUAAAAAACCAAAGGGCUGUGAGUAAGGGAGCUAUGUGGAAAGUGGGACUCUGAAGUGUAUUUUGAAAAUUAAUCGCCACCCUCUUCCAAAUUAUAGAAUUUUUUAAAAACAAGCUGUGGCCCUUUCCACUCUCUCCUGGCCUCUGGUGCUGCUCCUCUCUGCCGCCUUUCCUCCAUUCCAUGGCUUGAAACCUCUGCCUGAUGUGGCUCCUUCCUUUUUCCCAUUUGUCAAACCCUCUUCAAAGGAGGAACAGAUAAGACUGGGUCAGCCUAGUCAUGCCUCCCAACUGUGGUGGUAUAUGUGUACACACAUACACAGGGUGGAUGGAGAAGAGGUUGCUGAUUAAAAUACACUCCCCCUAUAAAGGGGAAGGGGGAGUGUGACACUUUCUUUCCAUGUUCAAGUGAAAAUAAAUAAUGUACCCUGCAGCCCUUUUCCCCUUUGCUUUCUUCUGGCUUGGGCAAAGGGCAUCAUAGGUGUAAGUGAAGUAAUUCCUUUUUCCUUCCCCCUCCUCCACUCCUACGCCCACUCCCAUGCUUGGGAGAAUGGGGCUGGGACAUGCACUGAGUGUUGCACUUUUAUUUAGGUAGGGAGGCAUGUUGAAUGAGCCAGGAGGUCUAGAACUGGAGCUUAGUCCAGCUGGUACAAUACCAACUCCCCUUCUAGUUCCCAAAGGCGAUGUCCAGACACAGACUUUAUGAUUAUUAUAUUUUUCAAUGCCAGUGCUGCUCAGCCCUCAGCAGAACUUCAGUUUCCAUGAAAUAAACAAUGACUAUAUAAAAUUC